GAGCCGCAGGCAGAGCGUCCGGCGGCCGGGAGGGACGCGGAGCCACAGCCCGACGCACGGACGGAGGGACGCCGGAGCCCGCCUGACCAUGUGGAAGCUGGGCCGGGGCCGAGUGCUGCUGGACGAGCCCCCCGAGGAGGAGGACGGCCUGCGUGGGGGGCCGCCACCGGCCGCCGCCGCCGCCGCCCAGGCGCAGGAAGCCGGCAGAAGUCCUUUGUACUGAAAACUGAAAGGCCUUUACCUGACGAGUGUAGAGAUAUGUUUGGUAUGUCUAGAAUUUUGUAAUUGAAAGGGCUCCCAGGUGGGCCCUGUGUGCCUUAGACGUGCCCUCCCCCACCCCCUCCCCCCCCCUCCCUUUUUCCAUUGCAGUGCUCUUUUUCAUGUACAAUGAAAUUUAGGUCAGAAAUCCAGCAUUCUGGAUCAUAAAAUAUCUCUUUCUGUUAAACGUGUGGCAACUUCCUCCUGAUGCUGUUAAGGCCGAAUGGAAUAUAAGGAUUUGUACCUGUCUUCCGAGGACUUGGAAAUAGUUUCUGAGCAGAAGAGUUUCUCUUAGGGUCUGGAGUUGUUUCUUCUUGAUAGAGAUUUUCUAUGAACGUUAAAUUCCAUUCCUAACUCAUGGAAAAUGGAGCCGAUUAUGUUAAGCGCUUAAAUAUGGUUACUAUCUGAACUUGUCUGAGAAAUUUCUUUUAGGUAGCGUUAGUGCUUACGUGCCUUUUUUUUUUUUAAUUUCAGAAUGUUAUAGUUACUCUAAACAGCUCUCUUCUUGAAUGUAAUGAUGAGAAUUUAUAUGUGGCUACAGAGUUAACUGCAGAAGCUACAAAUAACUAAUAUUGGUCAAAGAUGAGCCAUAUUAUUGUUUCUGGAUAGAGCCUUGAGAAUUUUAAACUGAGUCUUCCUAUGUUCUCCCAUUUUUCCUAAUGAAUCCUGAAACCCACUUUUUUUUCUUAAGUUUUUAUUUUUUAUUUUGAGACAGGGUCUUGCCCCGUUUACUAGGCUGGAGUGCAGUGGCGCAAUCUCGGCUCACUACGGCCUCAACCUGCCUGGGCUCAAGCUAUUCUCCUCUCUCAGCCUCUGUAGUAGCUGGGACUACAAGUGCGCACCACCUCACCUGGCUAAUUUUAAAAAACCGUUUUUGUGGAAAUGGGGUCUUGCUAUGUUGUCCAGGCAGAUCUGAAACUCCUGGGCUCACGUGAUCCGCCCGCCUCAGCCUCCCAAGGUACUAGGAUCACAGGCGUGAGUCACCACGCCUGGCCUUAAGUUCUUACUUUGAAAAAUUUCUAACAUGCGGAAAAGUAGAAGAAUAGGAGAUUCUUCCUCGUAUCCUCCAGCUAGAUUCAAUUGCUGGCAGUGCCUUCGUUAAAGCUCCUUUUCUGAUUUUCCCUUUACACAAUUGUCAUCUAUACUUUUUUUUUUUUUUUUUUGAGAUGAAGUUUCGCUCUUGUCGCCCAGGGUGGGGUGCAGUGGCGUGAUCUCAGCUCACUGCACCCUCCCGGGUUCAAGUGAUUCUCCUGCCUCAGCCUCUUGAGUAGCUGGGAUUACGAGCAUGUGUCACCACGCCUGGCUAAUUUUGUAUUUUUAGUAGAGACAGAGUUGUCCAUGUUGGUCAGGCUGGUCUCGAACUCAUGAUCUCAGGUGAUCUGCCCUCCUCGGCCUUCUGAAGUGCUGGGAUUACAGGCGUGAGCCACCGCGCCUGGCCUGUUAUCUGUACAUCUAAAGUGUGUGUUGGUUUUGGGGGGAAAAAACUUUAAUAGACUCUAUUUUUCAGGUAUCCAGUUUUAGGUGCCCAGCAAAUUUGAGGAGAAAGUACAGAGAGUUCUCAUGGAUCCCCAGCCCCCCACUAUCAUCACCCCCACAGAAUGGUGCGUUUGUUACAAUCUGUGGACCUACACGGGCUCAUGGUCCUCACCUGGGAGGGCUCACUCGUUGUGCAUUCUGUGGUUUGGACAAAUGUGUACUGACGUUUGCCCACCAUUGUAGUGUCACACACAGGAGUUUUGCUGCCUUAGAGACCCUCUGUGCACCCUCCCUCCCCGGAACCCCUGGCAAACAUUGAUCUUUGUACUGUCGCCAUAGUUUUCCAGAAUGUCAUUUGGUUGCAUUCACAGUGUGUAGCUUUUUCAGGUAGGUUUCUCUCACUUAGAAAGAUGCAUUUAAGGUUCCUGCAUUUCUUUUCACGGCUUGUAGCUCGUUUCUUUUUAGCACUGAAUAGUAUUCCACUGUUUGGGUGUACCACAGUUUAUCCCUUCACCCUCUGGAGGGCAUGUUGGUUGCUUUCACGUUUUGGCAAUUAUGAAUAAACAUCAGUUUAUUCAUAGACCAGCUGUAAACAUCAGGUGCAGGUUUUUGUGUGAAUUUAAGUUUCCAACUUGGGUAAAUACCUAGGAGCCUGAUUGCUGGAUUGCAUGGUGAGAGUGUUUAGUUUUAUAAGAAACCGCCAAACCGUCUUCCAAAGUGGCUGCACCAGUUUGCACUCCCAUGGACAAGGAAUGAGAUUUCCUUUUGCUCCACCUCCUUGCCAGCAUUUGGUGCUGUCAGUAUGUAGACUUUGUCCAUCCUAGUAGGUGUGUGGUGGUUUCUCUUUGUCUUGAAUUGCGAUUCCCUGAUGAUAAAUGACAUGAGCAUCUUUUCAGACGCAUACUUGUCAUCUGUGUCCCUUUUUUGGUGAGGUGUCUGUUUAGAUCUUUCUCCGCAUUUUUUAAUUAGGUGGUUUGAUUUCUCAUUGUUGAGUUUUAAGAGUUCUUUGUAUGUUUUGGAUACUAGUUCUUUAUAUGUAUGUGUUCUAUAAAGAUUUUCUCCCAAUCUGUGGCUUCACAUUCUCUUGACAGUGUCUUUUUCAGAGCAGAAGUUUUUAAUUUUAAUGAAGCUUCACUAUGAAUUAUUUCUUUGAUGGAUGUGCCUUUGGUAUUAUAUUGAAAAAGCCAUCACUGUACCCAAGGUUUUCCCAGUUAUGUGCUAGUUGUGAAUUUUGACUGUGGUUUUUAUGUUACUUUAUUAAGGUUAUCCAAAGUUUGUGUUGAAAAACAUUGCUAUAUAAAAAUAGAGAAAAUUUGUGUUAAUUAUGACAGAUUAGUCUUAUUCUAAAUUUAGUUAAUUUCUUCAAGAGGACUGAUCUUUAUUGCAAAGCUAACUUAGAAUUAAGAUGUUAGAAUUAAAUUAGAAUUAAAUUUUGAAAUUCAUGAAGAGUCAUAAAACUUCUGCCUACAAAAUUUUAAAGUUGAGAGAAGUAGGAAUUAAUAUGCAAAUAGGAUUUAAUGAAUCUGUUAAAUUCACUGUCAUGUUAGAAGUUCUCAAUUCUGUUUCAUUCUUGGUCUUUUGUCCUACCCUCCAAAUCUGUCAGUCAGUGUGAUGUUAAACGUGCAGGUUGAGAGCACAUUCUGCUUGAUUCUAGAAAGGCAUUCAGUUUGCAAUCAUAUCCGUCCUGUUGCCUUUCUUGAACAUCAGGUUACACACCUUUUUUUUUUUUUUUUUUUUUACGUGAAAAAGUAGAUAAUAUUAGGUUCCAAUAAAUUUGAAAUGUGAAGCAUUCAAAAUUACUUAGAUUUAUGGGACACUUAACUAUUACUAAAAUAAUUUUAACAUUUUAGAAAAUAAACUUCUCUGAGAAUCUUUUUAGGCUAUGGGCCCUUUUUUUUGGUCAUAAAUACACAUCUAUUUUGUAUUAACAUAUAACCGCAAGGUUUGUAAGGAGAAUCAUUCAUUGCAAUCCUCCAACAGAAAGACGCAAGUUUUCAUGAAUCUAAUGUUACUUGAAGAAAAACUGCUAAUGCAUAUGGUAAAAUAUUUGUUGAGAUUGUCAGGUCUUAACUUCUUCAAAGUUUCUAAUGGGAAACAUUGUUAAGCUCUUUUGUAUAUCUGUCCAUGAAACAUUUAUGCAGAUACAUAGGUGUGUGUUCAGAAACAAAGAUUUGCUGUCUCACUGUUAACAUUUUUCUGUACCUUGAGUUCCCUUCAUAAUAUGUGUCUCAUGGAGUGCUUCCCGUUUCAGUACUGCUAGUUGGAAAAAAUCCAUUUUAAGGCUGUGGGAUACUAAAUGAUAUUAAAUUUCUGUGACAAAAUUUAUUUCAUUGGGCCUCUUACGGUGAAUAUAAAGGUUGCUGAGCCGUCUUCUAACCUCUGCCCUCAAAGUUUUAUGCAAAUAGUAGAGAAAAGAAGUGCAGAGAUCUGUUCAACAUGGAUGGUUUAGAUGGGUCUGACAUGGACAGUGUAGAAGAGUUCAUCAGUUGCCUCUAAACUGGAUUGCAUAGGGAUUUGGCUAGGCUUAACUAAUGGCUUUCUAAACAAAACUCAGAAUUUUUGACAUAUUUUCACUUACAAAUUUAAAAAGCUUAGACAUAUUCUGUAGACAUUGCAAAGAAAAAAGACAUCAAGGAGUGUUUCAGGUGUUUUAAAAUCAUGCUUGGAGAUGGGGAGAGCCAAGGAAUAGUGAAUCUUAGUUUAGAUGACACAAAGUCACACUUUUAUGACACUGUGAGGCUCUGUGACGUUUGCUUUAGUGGUGUCUGGGAAGAAAGAAGUGGAGUAACGUAUUGACGAUCGCUCUGAAAUCCAGAAAAGGCCUGAUGUUCUGCUGGAGGGCGGGUAUGUGGGGAGGCAGAGGCCUUUCUCUCCCUGCUUGUAUAGCUAACAUUUUGUUACUGUUUUCCGUUAUUUCUCUUUAGAAAUAAAGCUGUUUUCUUAAGCAGACAUUAACCUGCAGUAAACACCUUCACACCUGCCUUUUCCCAUUUGCAGUAAGUUGUAGCCCUUACCAGUACAUGAAGAGCUUCCUCAUUCUUUCGUCUGUGUUUGUGUGUUAAAUGUUAUACAGUCAUCCUAGUUCAUUCAGGCCACUGUAACAGAAUAGGAUAAACUGGGCAGCUUCAACAACAAACAUUUAUUUCUCCAGUUCCAGAGGCUGGAAGUUUUAAAUCAGGGUGCUUCGUUCUUGGUGAGGGGCUGCUUCCUGGUUUGCAGAGGCCACUGCCUUCACACUACAUCCUCUCAAGGCAGAGGGAGCUCCAGCUUCUUACCACCAUAUUAGGACACUCAUCCCAUCGUGCCGGCCCCACCCUCGUGACUCCCAUCUCACCCUGAUCACCUCUUACAUACCCACCUGCACAUGCCAUCACAUGAGGGGAUGUGAGUUCUGGGGACACAAACAUUCAGUCCACAGCAAUUGCAUUUCCUUACGUGGAUAUACAGGAUUUUAAAUACAAAUUGAAAAAACGAGUCCCCUAUUGAUGCCUUCAGGGGGAUAUUUCUAGUCUCUUUCUAUUAUAGGCCUGCAGGAUAGUUAUUUCACAAGUCUAGAAGUGGAGCUGUCCGAGGAUGCGUGCAUUUGUGGUUUUGAUGGAUGUCUCCAAAUUGCCCUCUGAAAGAGGCGGUCCUGGUUUACGUUCCAACCAGCAGCAUAUGCGAAUGUUUCUCACCAGUGUGGUGAGAUGCGCAUGUCUUCAAGAUUUUAGAUCUGAUGGGGGGAAAAGUUGCAUCUUAAUGUGAUUUUAAUUUGCCUUUCUCUUAUUUAUAUUCAAUAGCUUCUUAGAUGUUCACAAGCCUAAUGAAGACUUCUAAAGACUUCUCCCCCAGUCCCACUACCAUGUCAUUGAAUGUAUGGAACUGUAGUCAAGAUAACUGUAUUUGCAUGAAAAUACAGUUGGGUAGUUUAGAUUUGGACUUGGUUUCUGGUGAGCCUUGAUUGAAUCUACACCCUAUCUCUGCCUUUUGUUGAGCCACUUGACCUAGCCAAGUAUCAGUUUUGUUUUUUAGCUGUAAAAUUGGGAUAAAUAGAGCUAUCACUAGUGUUUAUUGAGGCGGUGCUUAGCCCCUGUUCAUAAAUUCUUGAUAUGGGUUGGUGCCACCAUCUGACACAUGGGCACAAAGGAGGAGGGACCGGGAAGGCUACACAGCUGCCAACAGACUCUAUCUGACCCAGCUUUAGUCAGGACCUCGCUUUUGUCCUUCCCAGCCUCAGUAGAAGUCCCUGCAGUGCGAACCUCCUCACCCUUGAUGUCUGAUUGAGUUCCUCAUCCCCUGGCCUUGAUGUCUGAGUUCUUGGCCCACCUGUAGCAAGAAUCUCCCACCCUUGAUGAAGUCUUCUCUUGGUCACUUCCCAUCCCGAGACUCCUUUGCGGUUGGCUGCAAAUCACAGCUGUCUUUGCCUGUUGGGAGCUGAACCAAACCUCUCCUCUAUUGAGAUAGCCUUGAUUGGAGUCUCCCUGUUUUAACAAUGCCGCAGAAGCUUUUUCUUUAUCAGUGGUGAAAGGUUGCAGACAUUUUGUUUUAAAAACAAAACCUCUUCCCAACCAAGAAAACUUAACAAUAUAGGAAGAGAAAUAAAAUAAUUUUAUUAUGAAGGAGCACUUAGCUAGGAUGGGACACAUCAUAGGCACAGAUUGUGAAGAUGAAAGAAGUCUUACUCUUUUAUAUAACCAAGUAGGUAAAACCCAUUGUAUUCAUGUUUUCAAGAUAAAAUUGCUAAAUUUAUCCUAUCUUUACAGGGAGGCAGGAUUUGCAACUUGGAGUCAGGUGACAGCUGAAGUUAGGCUCGUCUCCUCUGGGAAAUGUCCUCUUUUGUUUCAGGUAGUUGUGAGACUGAUAGGAGGCUAAUUUAGCAUUCGACUUUAAAGGAGUCAUAAUUCUCAAACCCCGGUGAAUUCUUACUUGUUUACAAGACCAAUGAAGACUUCUAAAAACCUCGUAGUCCCCAUGGCCAGUGUGUGCAAACCAGGCUGUCCUGCCCCUGGGAUGAAAUGAAAAAGUGAAAAGUAAAUGAAGUCAUCCAUAUCCAGCCCUUAAUAUUUUUCUCUGGCAAACAGACACACUAAAAGAAGAAAAAGGAGGUCUUGUUAUUAAAUAAUAGAAAUAGUUAAUGCUUUUUACUGACUUAGGAUUUGGUUUUCUGGUAUCCCUUGCUCUGGAAUGUGCUCAUUGCCCGAGUUGAUGUGGACAGUGGGGUGUGGUGCAGGCAGGAGGGUCCUGGGACAGCUGCAUUCAGGCACUUCUCACUUGUGCGACAGGCAUUCGGACAUCACAAGCCUCUCUGGAGGACCAUUUCAUCCUAGGCUGAAUGCUCAGUGCUGUAUCCCCAAGACCAGGCAGGGAGCCAGCCCAGGAAGGGAGCCAGGCCCACGUGGGGCUCAGCAGUGCCCCUGAGAGGAGUGUACCUGGUGUGGGGUUUCCACAUUACGGCACCUGAUGGGAGCUGCAGAAUUGAGUCAGGGUGGGAACUCUGGAGUCUGGAGCGGGGAGCAGGAGUUCUCCAGCCUUAGGGGAGCUGAUCUUGAUGCAGAUUCUUUCUUGGGUAAACAGAUAUUUGUAGGGUUAGUCUCAUUGGACUCUCAUAUGAGCUGAGUCAGAUACUCAGUCAGCAGAAGCACUUGAGUCAAGUCUCUGUGGGUGAUUACUUGAGAGGAAGCAGGAAGGGUCAGUUACGAUAUUAUAGAAGGGAAGGAGGAUCCUGGGCGCUGCUUAUUCGCUCCGGAUUCAGCUGGCUCCUCUUAACUGAUGCUUGGGGAGCUCCUGCCUGUGGAACAGAGUGGUGCUUUCCUCCACUGAAACAUAGCAAAACAUUUUCUGGUGGCCACAUUAAAAAGUUUUAAUUCAAUAUUUAAAAUUUGAUAUAUUCAGCAUAUUACAUCAAUAGGUAAUCAAUAUAAAAUUUGUUAGAGAUCCUUUACAUUUUUUUCAUACUCUCAUAUCUAUGUGUAUUUUACAUUUACCAGCACAAGAUAUUAAUAUGUAUCAAUUUGUAUGCCAAGUUUUCUUCAGAAAUACUUGAUCAGUAUUUAGAGUUUAUAAAAUGUACAGGUGAAAAAACAGGUUGCUUUAUCUGAGUUCUUCCAAACAUACUUAAAAGUUUUCCAGUAUGGAAUGUUUUUAACUUGAAAUUUGAAUAAUUAAAAACUCAGUUUGACUAGCCCUAUUUCAGGUCCUCAGUAGUGUUUUUAGUGAAUGCCAACUGAUUUGGAAAGCACAGCUCUAGAAUCUUCUCCCAGACUCAGAUCAGCUCACUAAAGACGGUGGUGGAUUCUUCUACUUGCUUGGGCCUGUGGAAUUCCUCAAGCAAUUAGCUAGGUAAAUUCCAGGUGUCUCAACUGUGUGCUUUUAGUAAGCCACUGAAGGGUAGAAUGAUGAGGGCUUAAAUAUCUGCCUUUCAGGCCUUAGCAUAUUACUCUGUAUAAUCUUCACCUGUAAAUGUUAAUAAUAGGUUGAAAUUUUUAUUCCUGAGAGUUUAAAACCCUAAUUGAUAAGGUGUACUUUUACUGAUUUUUGCUAGGGCUUAAGGUGGCAUGACUUAGAAUGUCUAAAAGCUGCUAUUCUUAUUAGAGUUAGGCUGUGGGUUUCACUUUGUGAGUCAGUCACUGUCUUGAAAACUGAACGUCACUGAAUGUGGAGCCCAGCUUGCUCAGCCAGGGCUGGUGGGUUCCACCCCUACACUCACACCUGCCUCGGGUGGGCCCACCCCUACGCUGAGACCUGCCUCGGGUGGGCCCACCCCUACACUGAGACCUGCCUCGGGUGGGCCCACCCCUACGCUGAGACCUGCCUCGGGUGGGCCCACCCCUACGCUCAGACCUGCCUCUGGUGGGCACUUGUCCAUAUGGUGGGAGGCCCUGCAGUCUGUCUUCUGCUUUUUUAAGAUCACCUGUUGGGAGGAAUGGGCGACUUGGCUUUACGUCUGCCUUUGGGGAGUGGAUGUACAUGUGGGGCUCAUCAGCCUUGUCUUAGGAGUUAAAAGCCAAAGACUGAAGCUCAAGAGGAUUUUACCUGUUAUUUCAGAGUGAGUCAAGAUGCAGUCCACGGACCAGGGACACUUCCUUUUUCUUUCCUGUCUGCUCAGGGCAGGGAGGUCGUUUUAUGUUCGUUUUAUCUGAUCCUUCACCCCACGUUAGCUGGGGUUCUGUCUUGGUGCUGUAUAUAACCAGGCGAACCACAGUUUCUGCUUUGGGAGUUCUGUGGGGGUUGCUGUGAGGGAAGACUGCCUCCUCUCACCUUGGCUUUGUCUAGAAAUGGUUGGACCAUGAGCUAGGGUGGUGCAGCUGCUCCCAAAGACUUGGGAACCAGGCGAGUGUGUGGACAGCCCGCAGACCAGUUUGAAUCUAAGGAGAGGCCUUGGGGGCUGUGGGUGUGGCUUUUUUCAAGAUAUUAAUAAAUGUAUAUUAAAACCAUGAUGUAGCUUUCUAAUCUUUCAGAUGGAAGUACAAUAUUCUGUACAAAAAUGUUAUAGACUAAAUGGCAGAUAUUCUAGUUCUAGUGUUUGAAAGAUAACGAGUCCUUUUAUCAAGGCUGCUGUUGUGGGCAGAGAAUGGAAUGCUUUUUACUCAGAAUGCGUUGUGUCGUUUUUAGUCAGAGCGUGUCUUGGUUUGGAGGAUAGAAUCCUGGAUAAUGAUACUGGUGCCUGCCAUGUGCUGGGCAUUGGAGUGAGUGCUUUACAGCUAUUGCAGCUUCUCACAAUAGCCCAAAAAGUAGUUACAGUUCAUAUUCAUUAUUUGUGGAUUCCAUAUUUGCAAUUUCAGCUUCUUGCUAAAAUUUAUUUGUAAUCCGCAAAUCAGUACUCACAGUGCCUUCAAAGUCGUCCACAACUUGCAGAGCAGCAAACACUCAUCAUCACCCAGCGAGCUCCUUCCCAGCUGAGGCAUGUGUCUUUCCUGCAGUCUAUUGAGAACUACCUUUUUUUUACAUGUUUGUGCUUGCGUAUGAUUUCACUGUUUUUCACAGCCCCCAAGUAUAGUGCUAAAGCACUGGCUAGUGUUCCCAAGCACAAGAAAGCUGUGGCACUCCCUACGGAGGGAGCACCUGUGUUAGAGAUGGCUCAGGCAUGAGUUACAGGGCUGGUGGCUGAGAGUUCGGUGUGAAUGAAUCAACAGCAGGUAUUAAAGCAGGCAUCUUUAAACAAAUACAUGUAAAACAAGGUCACACAUUGUUGAUGAAAAGUUGUUAUUCAGAGGCUCGCGGGAACCCUAGCCUUGUGUUUCCCUUAACAGCAAUAAUUUAGUAUUUGCUAAUUGACUGUGGCAACUUUGUACAACAUAACUACUGUGAAUAAUGAGAUUAAACUGUAUUUUAUAUUCGAUGAUCUUAGAGAAGUUAAAUAACUCGUGUAAAGUUACAACCUUGUAAAUAAUUUGUGUUAGUAGCCACCAGUAGGAAUUUGAAUCCAAGUUUCUCUGGGUUUAUAUUCUUUGUUGAAUUCUCUUACCUUAUAGGUUAUGACAAAUUUCUGAUACCAUUUUUCUUCAUUUUCCAAUUUUUAAAAAUAUUAAAUAACUAGGGCUUCAACAAUCAGUGCCUUUUGAAAGCACUGAUAAAAUUGUGUUUUGGCUCAAUUUUCAAUACAGUAAACAUGACAGUGUACUUUUAAUUUUUGUCAUGCUUGAGUUUUGUAUUAAAGAGUUUCUUGUAUUAAAGAGUCUUACUAUGGGAGAUAAACAGUUCUCGGUAAAUUAGCAAGUGAGAAGCGCUAGAACAUUGCGAGGAAAGAGAACCGGUGUACAUCUGCCUACCCUAUACUUUAUAUACUUCCCUUUUUUCUUCGUGAUCGGGGGAGGGGGAUAGAAAAUGAAGCAGUUGAACUGACACAGGAGGGCUGUACAGGGAAGAACUGGGAAAAUCCCAUUAAGGAGUGGAGGCUUCAUUUCUUAGCUGAAUGUUGAAGAAUUCUGAGUAACCCCUUGGUUGUAUUUUGCAAAGACUACCUGUUUAAGGAGGAGGGGUUGGGGGCAAGAUGCCGAUGAAACGUCUGGGGUUCUAGUCAGGGAGGUCAGCUGUGAAAUGAGAACCUGAGUUUCAGAUGGAAGAUUUGUCAGGACAUGUAGGAAAAGGUGAGCUUGCCAAAGAGUGCUGAUCAGAGUUGGUGCCUUUGGAUGUGGAGAUGAAGGCAGAAAAGCAGCUGCAGGUGAAAGUUUUGAGCUAGGGUUGUCAGGAGAAGGGCGUGCCCUGACAGUCGCAAGGAACUCCCUGGGGUGGCCUGGCUGUGGGAGCAGCCCAAUGAGGCUGCGAUGGACGUGCUGGCUUUGAAAUGUUACCUGCUGUCCAGAGUUGAGGAGCCCAGCAGUGACAUGGGGUCAGAAGGGAGAGGCUUAUGUGCUUCUGGCUUGUGACACUGUCAAAAAUGUACAAGAACCUGGUUCUCCACUUCAGAACUCAUAAUUUGUUGUUGAGUGGUUGAGACCAGGAAGAACAAGGGGAGACAGCAUGGUGCUAGAAAAGCCUCUCUGAAGUGGUCUGGAGGCAGGCCUGGGUCCCAGCGCUGGUACUCAUUUUGGGACUUUGGGGCAAAUGAGUUCCUCUCUCCAGACUUCCUGUUUUAAGUAAGGGCUCUAGAGCAGGAGUCAGCAAACUUUUACUGUAAAGGAAGGGAUAGUAACUGUUUUAGGCUUUGGGGUCCAUGCAGUGUCAGAACCACUCAGCUCUGCAGUUGCAGGUGAAAGCAGCCGUAGGCAACUUGUAAAUGAACGAUCGUGGCUGGGUUCCAGUAUAGUGACUUUAUUUACAAACACAGGCCGUUAUUUGCUGACCCUUAGUUUAGACUAAAGGAUCUUUGAAAUCUCUUCUGACUGUAAGGUAACUUAUUAGAGUUUGUGAUACAGAAUUUGUUGUGAUUUAGGGUAAAAAUAGGAAGUCUUAAUGCUAAACUCAGAAAUAAAUAGCAUAGUCAUGAAGCUGACUUAUAUUCUUCCGGAGCUUCCAUUGUAUUAGCAAGUGUGCAUUUGUAUAGUUUUAAGCGCUUUUGCAUAAAUGGUCUUAUUUGGUCCUUAUCCUAUGAUAAAAUGAACAAGAUGAUACUCAAGGAGAAAACAUUUAGAACAGUUGUGAUUGUAUUCAUGGUCUUCACCCUAGCAGAGUAUAGAAGCUAGAAGAGCUGGAGUGCAUUUCUGUAGUCAGCAAGAACUGUGUGAUGGGUUCAUCAUCUUGCUAGGGAGCCUGGGGGCUAAUAUGUGCCCUUCUGAGACAGAUUGCAGGUUUCCCCCAGUAGCAGGUUUCAGUGGGUGCAUGGCUGCCACACAGCCUGAAGUCCCAGCAUCCUUCACCCUGCAAGGCUCAUGACUGAGUGCUGGCCACCACAUGUGAGCAGAUGCAACACAGGCACCUUCCUGGAUGUGUCCUGCUGCCUCUGUUUCCCCUUCACAGAGGUUAGUGGAUGUGGUGCACUCUCUUUCACCCUAUGGAUGAGAGCAGUGUCCAGAGGUGGCAGAGGAAUUAAAGGCAAGAACCUGGAUUUCUGACACUGUUGAACACCUAACUGUUCUCCUGGACUUAGGAGAAAAAGAAAUAUAAACCAUGUCUUUUGUUUGUUUUGUUCUGCUAUAGCAGCAAAGUGUAUCACAGUCAGGAGAUUUUAUUACGCAACCACCGCAGGGCCCACUGUCAGAGUACUGCUUGAAAUCCCCCCAUUCCUGUUCCAAUUUCUUAAACCAUAAAAUACUAGGUUGAAAUAAUAUGUGGUGUGAUUCAAUGUUUUCUUGUAACUACUCACAUCUCCUUUUAGCUAUUCUUUGCCAGAUAUUUGGCUGUGGUUAAUACUAAGCUUGUGGACUGAAGAUGAUUAAUAUUUCAAAAUAAAGUUUUAUAGUGAUAUUUUUAAAAAAUGAAGUUUUGUCCCCACAGUAUAACUCAGACAUUUGUUUGAUGUGGAAAGAAGUUGUGCCAAGAAAUUUUAGAGAAAAGACAGUCUGUAACUGUGAUUAAAGAUGGCAUCCUUACGCCUUUUCAUUUUUGUCGUAGAUAAAAAGUGUCCGUAUGUGUGGUUUCUUCUGACACCAACCAAUUCUUCAGUACCAGCUGGGUGUCCUACAAUUCAGUUUCCUUCUGACAUUCCCUUCCCAGAAUUAGCACAGAUCCUAUGGAUUAAGGAGUCAUUCCCGCAAGACUGCACCCACUUCAGAUGCCAGAUACCAACGGGUGCCCAAUUCACCAUAAGUCUCUUAUGCCACUCCACAUAAAAUGUCUGAUGUCAGCACAAUGGUGGAGUGGAAAGUCCCGGACCUUGUUCCCCCACGGACUCUGACUGACAACAAUAUACAGUCCAAAAGGAUGUAUGAGAAUUACAGAAACCAGUUUAGAAGUCACAGUACCCCAGGCAAGCUCAAAGCCAAGAACAGCUGCAUUGAAGUAGGAGAAAAAAAAAGCCAUUUAAUUUCACCUGCCUUUCCCUGAAGGUGGCACAGCUUGGCAUGAUUGGUAGUAAACACCCAACUCUCUGCUGGGUAGAAAGUGAAGAAAGGAAGUCCACCAUUCUGAAUUUUGGGGGGUCACCUGAUGGACUGGUUUCUGUCUCUCCUGACUCAGUGCUGACUGGGAACUGGCAUACUUUGGAUGCCUGGGGGCUUCAGAGAAAAAAGAGUUAACUGGCUUUUUGCAGCAUCAGAGACUCAGCAGUGCUGCGGAUGGAGGUCGGGACAGCUCAGCACAGUCAGGAGAGAGCGUGUGGUUCUUGGCUUAUCCCUUGGGCAGGAAUGGGAAGAGUGGAAAGUGCAUUUAACAUUCUGGCUUUUCAGGGGGACUGCCCAAGAGACUGAUUCCUGUUUUGCCUGACUCAGAGCGCUGAGAGAACCAAGGGUAUGUUGGAUGUCUGGGGGCUGCUGAGAACAAGCGAGAGCUCCACAGCCUGUUGCCCUGCCAGACAACUUGCAGUGCCACAGACAAGCACCAGAGGGAUCGAGAGAUUACAAGCAACUGAAAAGAAACUGGCAGACCUCUCUAAUUGGGACAUUCCAUGUACAAGCCCAGAGAAGAUUCAUCCCCAGAAAAGGUUUGAGAGGCCCCAGAAUCUCUAGCUGAGCUGAUUGGUGAAGUUCUUCUCCUGUACCAAGCCAGUCCAUAAAGACUGGGAGAGGUGGCUGUUUUUUCAGAUACCCCAAAUCCCAGCAAAAAAAUAAUGAGACAUAUGAAGAAACAGAGAAAUAUGGCCCAAUUAAUGGAACAAAAUAAAUCUCCAGAAUUUGACCCUAGAGAAACAGAGAUAAAUGAAUUAUCUGACAAAGAAUUCAAAAUGAUCAUCUUAAAGAAGCUUAGUAUGCUGUGAGAGAACAGAGAUAGUCAAGCAAAUGAAAUCAGAAAAAAUGCAAUAACAAGAAUAUCAACAACAAGACAGAACUAUAAAAAAAGAACCAUACAAAUUCUGCAUCUGAGAAAUAACUGAAUUGAAAAAUUAACUAGAGGGAUUAAAAAGCUGACCCAGUCAUGCAGAAGAAUCGUCAAACUCAACAGCUCAUUUAAAUUCAUCAAAUCAGAAAAAAAAAAUGAAAAGUAAAGCCUAAGGGAUUUAUGGCACACCAUUGAGUGGACCAAUAUACAUAUUGUAGAAGUCCCAAAAGGAGAAAAGGGAGUAGAGAGCUUAUUUGAAUAAAGAGUGGUGCAAAACAUCCCAAAUAUGAGGAAGAAAAUGGACAUCCAGAUUCAAGAAUCUCAAAGGACUCCAUGUAGGAAGAAACCAAAGAAAGGGUAAAGAAGCCCACACUGAGAAAGAUUUUAAUCAAAUUGCCAAAAGUCAGUGGUAGAGAAUUUUGAAAGAAGAAAGAGAAAAGCAACUUGUCAUAUAACAAGGGAGCUCCCAUAAGAUUAUCAGCAGAUUUGUCAGCAGAAACAUUACAGUACAAAAGGGAGUGGGGUGAUACAGUUCAAGUGUUGUUAAAAAUAAAAAUACACCCAGCCAGCCAAGAAUACUGUAGCUGGCAAAACCAUCUUUCAAAAAUGAACAAAUAAAGACCUUCCCAGAUAACCAAAGCCAAAGAAGUUCACCACCACUAGAUCUACCUUGUAAGAAAUGCUAAAGAGAUUCUUUGAAGCUGAAGUGAAAGGAUGCUAAAUAGCAAUAUAAAAGUAUAUGAAAAAACUCUCUGGUAAAGGGAAAUAUGUGGACAAAAACAGAAUCCUAUAAUAUAGUAAUGGUGGUGAGCAAACAACUUUAAAUUCUGGUAUAGAAUUAGACAAAAGCAUAAAAAUAACUAAAACUAUGUUAAUAGAUAAAAAUAUAAAAUACUCGAUUUGGUUUUUUAAUUUUUAAUUUUCGUGGGAUCAUAGUAGGUGUGUAUAUUUAGGGGAUGUGAUGGUUAAUACUGAGUGUCAACUUGAUUGGAUUGAAGGAUGCAAAGUAUUGAUCCUGGGGUAUGUCUAUGAGGGUGUUGCCAAAGGAGGUUAACAUUUGAAUCCUUGGACUGGGAAAGGCAGACCCACCGCCAAUCUGAGUGGGCAUCAUCUCAUCAGCUGCUGGCACAGCCAGGAUAUAAAGCAGACAGAAAACAUGAAAAGGCUAGACUGGCCUAGCCUCCCAGCCUAUAUCUUUCUCCUGUGCUGGAUGCUUCCUGCCCUCAAACAUCAGACUCCCAAGUUCUUCAGUUUUGGGACUCGGACUGGCUUCCUUGCUCCUCAGCUUGCAGACAUCCUGUUGUGGGACCUUGUGAUUGUGUGAGUUAAUACUACUUAAUAAAUUCCCCUUUACACACACACACACAUAUAUACACACACAUAUAUACACACAUAUACACACACACAUAGUUAUAUAUAAAUAAAUAUAUGUAUAUAUCCUAUUCUAUUCCUUUAGAGAACCCUGACUGGUACAGGGGUACAUGAGAUUUUGAUACAGGCAUAUAAUACAUAAUAAUCACAUCGGAGUAAAUGAGGUAUCCAUCACUUUAUGCAUUUAUCCUUUGUGUUACAAACAAUCCAAUUAUACUCUUAUUUUUUAAAAGUACAAUUAUUUAAUAUUAUUGGCUGUAGUCAUCCUGUUGUGCUGUCAAGUACCAGAUCUUAUGCUAACUAUAUUUUUGUAUGUUGAUGUUGAUGGAUACUUAGGUUGCUUCCAAAUCUUGGCUGUUGUGAACAGUGCUGCAAUAUAUAUUGGAAGCACAGAUAUCUCUUUGAUAUAUUGAUUUCCUUUCUUUUGGGUAUAUAUCUAGCAGUGGGAUUGCUGGAUCCUAUGGUAGUUCUAUUUUUAGUGUUUUGAGUAACCUCCAAACUGUUCUCCAUAGUGGCUGUACUAUUUUACAUUCCCACCAAUAGUGUACAACGGUUUCCUUUUCUCCACAUCCUCACCAGCAUUUGGUAUUGCCUGUCUUUUGGAUAAAAGCCAUUUUAACUGAUGUGAGUGAUAUCUCAUUGUAGUUUUGACUUGCAUUCCUCUGAUGAUCACUGAUGUUGAAUACCUUUUCAUAUACCCAUUUACCAAUUAUAUGUCUUCUUUUGGAAAAUGUCUACUCAGGUCUUGUGUCCAUUUUUUAAUUGGAUUAUUAGGUUUUUUCCUAUAGAUGUGUUUGAGCACCUUUUAUAUUCUGAUUCUUAAUCCCUUGUCAGGUGGGUUGUUUGCAGAUAUUUUUUCCCAUUCUGUGUGUUGCCUUUCCAUUUGUUGAUUGGUCCCUUUGCUCUGUAGAGGCUUUCUAAUUUGAUGUGAUCCCAUUUGUCCAGUUUUGCUUUGGUUACCUGUGCUUGUGGGGUAUUAAGAAAUCUUUGCUUAGUCCAAUGUCCUGGAGAGUUUCCCUGAUGUUUUCUUUUAGUAGUUUCGUAGUGUGAGGUCUUAGAUUUAAGUCUUUAAUCCAUUUUGAUUUGAUUUUUUGUGUGUGUGUAUGGUGAGAAAUAGGAGUCUAGUUUCAUUCUUCUGCAUGUGGAUAUCCAGUUUUCCCAGAACCAUUUAUUGAAGAGAUUGUCCUUUUCCCAAUGUAUGUUCUUGGUAUCUUUGUAAAAAAUGACUUCACUGUAGAUGUAUGGAUUUGUUUCUGGGUUCUCUAUUCUCUUUCAUUGGCCUAUGUGUCUUUUUGUGCCAGUUCCAUUUGGUUACUCUAGCUCUGUAGUAUAAUUUGAAGUCGGGUAACAUGAUUCCUCCAGUUUUGUUCUUUUUGCUCAGGAUAGCUUUGGCUAUUCUGGGUCUUUUGUGAUUCCAUAUACAUUUUAGGAUUUUUUUUUUCCAUUUCUGUGAAGAAUGUCAUUGGUAUGAAUGGGAUUACAUUGAAUCUGUAGAUUGCUUUGGGCAAUAUGGAUAUUUUAACAAUAGUGACUCUUCCAGUCCAUGAACAUGAAAUAUCUUUUCAUUUUUGUGUCCUUUUCAAUUUCUUGCAUCAGUGUUUUAUAGUUUUCAUUGUAGAGAUCUUUAACUUCUUUGGUUCAGUUACUUCUUAGGUAUUUAAUUUUUUUUGUACUUUUUUAAUUUUAUUUUUUCAGAUUGUCUGCUUUUGGUGUAUAGAAAUGGCAAGUGUUUUUGGUCUGUUGAUUUUGAAUUUGUUUAUUAGUUUUAAUAGCCUUUUGGUGGAGUCUCUCUAACUCUGGGCCUCAAGCCAUCCUCCCAUCUCAGCCUCCCAAAAUGCUGGGAUUACAGACAUGAGUCACUGUGCCUGCCCUAUUUGGUUGAGUCUUUAGGUUUUUCCAAGUAUAAGAUCAUGUCUGCAAACAAGGAUUAUUUGAUUUCUUCCUUUCUAGUUUGAAUGUCUUUUAUUUUUUUCUGGUGUCUGAUUGCUCUAGCUAGGACUUCCAGUACUACGUUGAAUAACAGUGGUAAAAGUGGGCAUCCUUGUCAUGUUCCAGAUCUGAGAGGAAAGGAUUUCAUUUUUCCCUUCAGUAUGAAAAAUAGAGGAGAAGGGAAUAAGUCCAAAGCUAUUCUACAAGGCUAGUAUUGCCCUCAUAUAAAACCAGACUAAGACAUACCAAAAAGAGAAAACCACAGGCCAAUAUGAUGAACAUAGAUGUAAAAAUUCUCAAUUAAAUACUGGCAAACCAAAUUCUACAACAUACUAAAAAGAUAAUUAUGAUCUUUUUAUCCCAGGGAUGUGAGGAUGGUUCAGUAUAUGCAAAUCAACCAACGUGAUACAUCAUAUCAACACAAUGAAGGACAAAACCCAUAUGAUAAUUUCGAUUGAUGCUGAAAAAGCACUUGAUAAAAUUCAACAUCUCUUCAUAAUAAGAACGCUCAAAAAACUGUAUAGAAGGAACAUAACUCCACAUAAUAAUAGCCAUAUGCAACAGAUUCAUAGCUAGUAUCAUACUGACAACCCAGUGGUGCAUUUUAAAGAACUAGAGUCUGGGCAUGGUGGCUCACAUCUGUAAUUCUAGCACUUUGAUAGGCUGAGAUGGGCAGAUCACUGGAGGCCAGUAGUUCAAGACCAGCCUGGCCAACCUAGCGAAACCCUGUCUCUACUAAAAAUACAAAAAUAAGCUGGGCAUGGCUACAACAAAUACUGCAGAAAUUCAAAGGCUCACUAAAGGCUACUCACUAAAGGCACAAUAAAGGCAUAUUGUGCAACUAUAUGCCAAUAAAUUGGAAAAUCUAGAAGAAAUACAUACAACCUGUGAAGUUUGAACCAUGAAGAAAUCCAAAACCUGAACAGACCAAUAACAAUAAGAUCAAAGCCAGAAUAAAAAGACUUCCAGCAGAGAAAAGCCCAGGACCCAAUGGCUUCACUGCUGAAUUCCACCUAACAUUUAAAGAAAUACUAAUAGCAAUUGUACUCAAACUGAUUGGAGAGUUUCGUCCAUUUACAUUCAGUGUUAUUGAUAAAUAAUGACUUACUCCUGCCAUUUUCUUACUUGUUUUCUGGUUGUUCUGCGGUCUUUUCUUCUUUCCUUCCUUCCCGUCGGUGAUUUUCUCUUGUGGUAUGUUUUAAUUUCUUUUUAUUUUUUGUGUAUCCAUUGUAUGUUUUUUGAUUUGAGGUUACCAUGAGGCUUGCAAAUAAUAUAACCCAUUAUUGUAAACUGAUGACAAUUUAACACUUAUUGCAUUAAAAAACGAGCAAAAACUAGUAAAAACUCUACAGUUCCACUUCAUCCCCCUGAUUUCUCUUUGUUGUUUCCAUGUAUAUCUUAUUGUAUUACAUCUUAAGAAGUUAUUUUUAAUUGGUUUGUCAUUUAAAGUAUAAACUACAUAAGAUAUGAGUACUUUAACAGUAUAAUACAGUGUUAUAAUAUUCUGUUUUUCUAUGUACUUAGUAUUACCAGUAAGUUUUGUACCUUCAGAUAAUUUCUUCUUUCUAAUUAACAUCCUUUUCUUUCAAAUUGAAGAAUUCCCUUUAACAUUUCUUGUAGGACAGAUCUGGUGUUGGUGAAAAUCCUCAGCUUUUGUUUGUCUGGGAAGAUCUUUCUCCUUCAUGCUUGAAGGACAUUUUUGCCAGAUAAUCUAGGGUAAAAAUGUUUUUCCUUCAGCACUUUAAUUAUGUCAUGCCGCUGUCUCUCUUGACCUGUAAGGUUUCCACUGAAAAGCCUGCUGCCAGACCUAUCGGAGCUCCAUUGUAUGCUAUCUGUUUCUUUUCUCUUGCCGACUUUAGAAUCCUUUCUUUAUCUUUGGUCUUUAGGAGUUUGAUUAGUAAAAGCCUUGAAGUAGUCUUGUUUGGGUUAAAUCUGCUUGGUGUUCUAUAAUCUUCUUGUACUUGAAUAUAGAUGUCUUUCUCUAGGAUUGAGAAGUUCUCUGUUACUCUCCCUUUGAAUAAACUUUCUACCCUUCUCUCUCGUUCUCUACUUCUUGUUUAAGGCCAAUAACUCCUAGCUUUGCCUUUUUGAGGCUAUUUUCUAGAUCCUGUAAGCAAGCCUCAUUGUUUUUUAUUCUUUUGUCUCAUGUCUCCUCUGACUGUGUAUUUUCAAUAGCCUGUCUUCAAGAUCACUAAUUCUUUCUUCUGCCUCAUCAAUUCUACUUUUGAGACUGAUGCAUUCUUCAUAUGUCAGUUUAAUUUUUUAGCUUGUAAAUUUUUCAGAAUUUCUGCUUGAUGUUUUAAAAGCUUGAUGUAAGAACACUUAUUUCAAUCUCCUGGUCAAAUUUAUCUGAUAGGAUUCUGAAUUCCUUCUCUGUGUCAUCUUGAAUUUUGUUGAGUUUCCUCAAAGUAGUUAUUUUGAAUUCUCUCUGUGAAAGGUCACAUAUCUCUGUUUCUGAGGCCUUUAGUUUGUUUGGUGAGGUUAUGUUUUCCUGGAUGAUCUUGAUUCUUGUGGAUGUUCGUGUGUGUCUGGGCAUUGAAGAGUUAGUAAUUUAUUGUAGUAUAUGCAGUUUGGGCUUGUUUGUACCCAUCCUUCUUGGGAAAGCUUUCCAAGUAUUCAAAGGGACUUGGGUGUUGUGAUCUAAGUUUUUCGUCACUGUAUUAGGGGCACCCCAAGCCCAGUAAUGCUGUGACUCUUGCAGACCUGUAGACAUACCAACUUGGUUUUGGUUAAGAUCCAGGAUAAUUCCCAGGAUUACCAGGCAGAAACUCUUGUUGUUUUCUCUUACUUUCUCCCGAACAAAUGGAGUCUGUCUGUGCUGAACUGCUGGGAACUGGGAGAGGGGUGACACAAGCACUCUUGUGGCCACUGCCCUGGGACUGUGCUGAUUCAGACCAGAAGCUAGGACAGCUCUGGAUCUCGCUCAAGGCCCUGCUAUAACCACUGCCUGGCUACCACUUUUGUUCGCUAAAGGCCCUAGGGCUCUACAAUCAGCAGGUGGUGAAGUCAGCCAGGCUUAUAUCCUUCCUUUCAGGACAAUGAGUUCCCCCUGGUCCCUGGAUGUAUCUAGGGAUGCUGUCCAGGAGCCAGGGCCUGGAGUCAGAAACCUCAGGAAUCAACCUGGUGCUCUAUUCUACUGCAGCCUAGCUGGCACUCCAGCCACUAGACAAAGUCCUUCCCACUCUUCCCUCCCCUUUCCACAAGCAGAGGAGCCUCUCCCCUUGGCUACCACUGCCCCAGGCCCUCGGAGAGUAUUGCCAGGCUAUUGCCGAUGUUAACUCAAGGCCCAAGGGCUCUUUAGUCAGCUCGUGAAUGCUGCAAGGCCUAGGACAUAUCCUUCAGGGCAGUGGGUUCCCCUUUGGCCCAGGGCAAGUCCAGAAAUGCCAUCCAAGUAGGAAGGCCUGGAAUCAGGGACCCCAGGAGCUUGACUGCUGCUAUACCCUACUGUGGCUGAGCUGGUACCCAAGCUGAUUUUUAGUUCUUAUAAAGGUGAUUUUUGUGUAGAUAGUUGUUAAAUUUGGUGUUCCUUCAGGGAGGAUGAUUGGUGGAGGCUUCCAUUCAGCCAUCUUACUCCACCUCCAUUCCCCCCGAAAAAAUUAAUUUGUGAUAGGAAUAGCAUAAAGGGGAGACAUAAAGUAAUACAUUUAUAUGCGGGGUUAAGUUAAAUUAUCAGUUUAAAAUAGAUUAUUAUAACUAUAAGAUGUUUUAUGUAAUCCCUGUGAUAACCAGAAAGAAAAUGCCUAGGGGAUACAGAAAAGAAAAAGGAAUAAAAACAUUUCACUACAAAAUAUUAAAGGAAGUCAGCAAGAGAGGAAAAGAGGGUCAAAAUUACUACAAGACUUAAAGAACAUAAUUAACAAAGUGGCAAUAGUAAGUCCUACCCUAUCAGUAAUUACUUUCCAUGUAAAUGGAUUAAACUCCCCAACCAAAACUACGUGUGGUUUAAUCGAUUAAAAAAAGAUCCAAUCACAUGCCACCUACAAGAUACUCACUUUAGAUAUAAGGAUACACGUAAGCUGAAAAUAUGGAAAAAGAUUCCAUGCAAGAGAUAUUCCAUGUUCUCUACUAAAAGGGAGUAGGAGUGGCCUACUUAUAUCGGAUAAAAGUCAAAAACUGUCACAAAACACAAAGAAGGACUAUGUAAUUGCUGUGGGAUAAUUGAGGAAUCAGAGGCAGGGGUUGAGGAGGAAUUAUUUAAUUAUUUAGGUGCACCGAGUCAGUCGGAUUAACAUCCAAAGGACUGAGCCCCAAACAAAGAGUCAAGCUACCUUUUAAGCAUUUCAUGGGGCGGAGGGAGAUCUGUGCGGGGCAAAGCAUAUUACAGAAGCGAGAAACAAAGACAGUUAUUUAAUUAAGACAUGCAUUACAUUAUUUCUUACUUUUCAAGGAACAACAUGUUUUACGACUUGAGAUUAUCUGUCUAGUGACCUUAGAGCUGCACAGCUAGAGAAACAGAGUCUUCACAAUGCAUGGCAAAGGGAGAGAUGAGUCUCACUAGCCACAGAGAGAAAAACAGGCAGUUAAUUUUAAAGGACUCCAGCCCUUUCUCUUCCUCAAGGGGAAUUGGGUUUUCUUACAUACAACUGAGUUUUUGCUUACACAGUCUUUAAUUUCUUUUAAUUCCUGUUCCAUAAUGACAAAGGGGCCAGUUCACCAGGAAGAUAUAACGGUUAUAUCUGCAUCUGACAGCAGAGUGCUCAAAUGUGUGACAUAAACGUUUAGAGGAUUGAAGGGAGACAUAGUAGCACAAUGUAAAUAGGGGACUGUCUGACCUUGUAUGUAGAGAACCCUAAAGAUCCCAAACACACAAAAAAUGUUACAGCUCAUGAACAAAUUCAGCAAGGUUGCAGGAUACAAUAUCAACAUGAAAAGUCAGGCACAUUUUUACACUAAUAAUGAAAAAUCCCAAAUGGAAAUUAAGAAAACAAUUAAUAAAACACUUAUAAUAGCAUCAAGAAAAAAGGUACUUAGAAAUAAUGAAGGAGGUGAAAGACUGAAAAAAUAUAAAACAUUGCUGAAAGUUAUUAAAUAAGACAUAAAUAGACAGCCCAUGUUGAUGGUUUGGAAGACUUAUAUUGUUAAAAUGUCCAUAUUACCCACAGCAAUCCACUGGUUCAAUGCAAAUCUCAUUGGCAUUUUUUUUGCUGAAGUAGAAAAGAAAUUCUAAAGUUCAUAUAGAAUCUCAAAUGACCUGAAUAGCUAAAACAAUCUUGAGAAAGAAAAAAACAAAAACAAAAACUGGAAGCCUCACACUUUCCAACUUGAAAACAAAUUAUACAAGUACAGUAAUGAAAGCAGUAUGAUAUUGGCAUAAACACGGACAUAUAGAACAAUGGAACAGAGUAGAGAGAAAUAAGCCCUCAUGUAUAUGGUCACAUGAUCUUAAACAGGGCUGCUUGGAUUACACAAUGGAGAAAAGAUAGUCUCUUCAACAAAUGCUGUUGGGAAAACUGGAUAUUCACAUGCAAAAAAUGAAGUUGUAUCUUUUUUUGUUUUUUGGGACGGCAUCUCUCUCUCUUGCCCAGGCUGGAGUGCAGUGGUGUGAGCUCGGCUCACUGUAAGCCCCGCCUCCCGGGUUCACGCCAUUCUCCUGCCUCAGCCUCCCAAGUAGCUGGGACUACAGGCGCCCACCACCACGCCUGCCUAUUUUUUUUUUUUUUUUUUUUUUGGAUUUUUAGUAGAGACGGGGUUUGACCGUGUUAGCCAGGAUGAUCUCUAUCUCCUGACCUCAUGAUCCGCCUGCCUCGGCCUCCCAAAGUGCUGGGAUUACAGGUGUGAGCUGCUGCUCCCUGCCAAAGUUGGAUCUUUAACACCUGUACAAAAAUUAAUUCAAAAUAGAUUAAAGACCUAAAUCAGAAAUUAUAAAACUCCUAGAAGAAAACGGGAGAAAAGGUUCAGGGCAUUGGAUUUGGCAAUGAUUUCUUGGAUAUGACACCAAAACACAGGAAAAAGCAAAAAUAGACAAAUUGAAGCAUAUCAAAAUUUAAGACUUACAUGUAACAAAGGAAACAAGAAAGUAAAAAUGCAACGUUUGGAAUGGGAUAAAUAUUUCUCAGCCAUAUCUCUAAUAAGGGGUGAAUAUCCAAAAUAUUUAAAGAACUCCUAUGACCAAACAACAACAAAAAACCUGAUUAAAAAAUGGGCAAUGGACUUGAGUAGACGUUGGUGCACAGAAGAUACACAAAUGACCUAUAAGCAUAUGAAAAGAUGUUCAACGUUGCUAAUCAUCAGGGAAAUACAAAUCAAAACCAUGAUGAGAUGUCACCUCACAACCAUUAGUAUGGCUACAAUCAAAAAAGCAAAAUAACCAGUGUAACCAAGGAUGCGGGGAGAUUGGAACACCUGUGCACUGUUGGCAAUCUUGUAACAAUGAUUUAGCUGCUGUGGAAAACUGUAUAGAGAUUUAUCAAAAAGUUAAAAAUAGAAUUAUAUGUUUCAGCCAUCCCACUUCUGUGUAUAUAUCCCAAAGAAAGGAAAACAGGAUCUCAAAGAGAUUUGCACACCCAUGUUCAUUACAGCACCACUUAUAAUAAGAGGAGAAGCAGCCUCCAUGUCUGUGGAUGGAUUAAUAGAUAAGGAAAAUAUAGUACAUAUGUUCAAUGGAAUAUUAUUCAGCCUUAGAAAAGAAGGAAAUCUGAUAAUAUGCUAGUAUAUGGAUGAACUUGAGAAUAUUAUGCUUCAUGAAAUAAGCGAGGCACAAAAAAACAACUAAUGCGUGGUUCUACUUACAUGAGGUAUUGAAAGUAGUCAUGUAACUGAGCAGCUUGGCUUCAAACCGUGUUUUAAAAUGUUUUCUUUCCACUUUUCUCCCCAACCACAGGAUAUAACUUUGAAACAAAACUGCCUAUGUGUUUCCUUUCAUUUUGAAAUACAGCUUCUGAACGUGCUGUGACCUCCAUUCCCUUUCUUUCCCAUUCUGUGCCUUACACGCAUUUAUUUAGCUGGAUGCCGGUAAAGCACAUAAAUUGCCCACUUAUCUGGUCAUAUAUUUCCUUAGAAGCUUCAGGGGCCAGAUGCUGAUUCGGAUCAGACACCUCUGGCCACAGUGGCGCCAGCCCCUUCACCAGGUGGAACAAUAAUUCAAGAUGAGCCAUCAGGGUGGGUCACAUACCACUUGACAAUGCCUCGCCCCACUGCCUCUUCUGCAUUCCAAACCCUGUCUUUAAAAAGUACGUUCCCUCCACAAAUUGAAGAGUAGAUUUUUUCACUCUCUUUUAGUCACACCUCAUUAUUAUUUUGGGUUCUUUUUACAAGCAGUGAGCAACCCAACCCUUUGAGGGUUACAGCAAACUCUUAGAGAAAGCAGAAUGGUGGUCACGAGGGGCUGAGGGUGGGGGAGAGGGGGGUUUUUCAGUCUGUAUAUAGAGUUUUACGAGAUGAAAAAGUUUUAGAGAUCUGUUGUACAACAGUUUGCAUGUAGUUAACGCAAUUGAACUCUAUACUUGAAGGUAGUUAAGAUGGUAGAGUUGAUGUCAUAGGUAUCCAUGCUACCCUUGCUUCUACUCAGCUGACUCUAAAGUGGGGGUUUCCCAUGACUCUCUGUCAUGUCCAAUAGUUUACAGAACUCCAGAAAGCUCAUUUUUCAGGAUUGCUGGUCACUUGAAAGGAUACAGCGGAGGAACAGCUCAACAGAAGAGAGAUAGCAAAGGGGAAGGCAUGGGGAGGGCACACAGCGUCCAUCCCUCUCAACAUGCAUGCUCUCAGCACAUGGAUGGGUUCACUAACCUGGAAGCUCCAGAACUCUGUCAUUUAGCUUUUUAAAUGGAGGUUUCAUUCCCUAGGCAUGACUGAUUAAAUCUUUGGCCAUUGGUGACUGGAUUCAAUCUCUAGCCCUCCUUCUCUCUUUGGAGGUCAGAGGAGGAGGUGGGUGUGGGGCUGAAAGUUCUAGUCCUGAAAUCAAGGUGUUGGCAUUUCUGGUGACAGACUCCAUCCUGAAGCUCUACCAGCCUCCUGUCAGUCAUCUCAUUAGUGUACGAAAGGCAGUAAAUUCCAAUACUUUCAGGAACUCUGUGUCAGGAACCAAGGAUAAAGACUAAACAUUGAGUUUUUUAUACCAUACUCCAGUAUUUGAUUUGUUAAUAAAUUUGUAUGAAUUUCAAAUUAGACUUUCUAUUAAGAUAUUUAUGUAAAUGACCUUUUAAGCUAAAAAAAAAAUGGUGGAAUCUAUUUACUUUUCCAAUUUUUUUUCAUUUGCCCUAAGGCUUAGAAAGGAAUUUCUUUCCCUGAGAUCAGAUUCUUUUAGUUCCUUUAUGGCUUCAUUUAAAAGGAAUAACUCUUUAACUGGUCGAAGUUACUUUGCUGUGAAGAAAAGAUCCUUUUCUCUCAAAAUAGUUACUCAGCUUUCCUAGACUUUUGUUCUUUUUCCUUUUUUGUCAUGCACCUCUUACUGUAUACUAAAAUCUCUAUAUACAUGGGUUUGUUGGGUUUUCCAUCUGUUUUCUUUGUUCUUUUAUAUACUUUUAUUCCAUUUCUACAGUUGUCUUAGUGAAGUUUUCUAAUACAUUUAAUAACUGGUAGCACAGGUUACCUUUUAUUAGACUUAUGUGUACCCAUGCCUGUUGGCUUUGUUGUGUGUGUUAUUGAGCCAGUUAUUGUUGUCAUCUUCUCUUUUUCAAUAGACUCUUUUUUAUAGCAGUUUCAAGUUCACAGCAAAAUUGAAGGGAAGGCACAGAGUUCUUAGGUGCCUCCUGGCCCCUACCUUCCCUACCUUCCCUACCUUCCCUGCUACCAACAUCCCUCUCCAGAGCGGUGCCUUUGUUAAAAUUGACGAACAUACAUUGAUGCAUCAUUGUUAGCCAAAGUCCAUAGUUGACAUUAGUGUUUACGCUGGGUGUUGUCUGUUCUGUGAGUCUGGAUGAGUGUACGGUGGCACGUGUCCACCAGUGUAGCAUCAGGCCUGGUGGUUCCACUGCCAUAAGAUUUAAAAUUCCACUGUGCUCCACCUUUUCAUCCCUCCCUCCCCUGAACCCUUUGCAACCACGGAUCUUUUUACUGUCUCCAUAGUUUUGUGUUUUCCAGAAUGUCAUUUGGUUGUAAUUACACAGUGUGUAGCCUUUUCAGAUUGGCUUCUUUCACUUAGUAAGAUGUAUUUGUUGGCAGAAAAAUCCAAACUCUGUAAAAUAUUUGAAUAGAUUUAUUCUGAGACACAAUGACAAUUUUGCUGUAUAGCCUCAGGUGAUCUUGAGAACAUGUACCCAAGGUUGUUGGGCUACAGCCUGAUUUUCUACAUUUUAGGGGGACAAAAGUUACAGUUUUAAAUCAAUACAUGUAAGGUAUAUAUUGGUUUGGCCUGGAAAGGCUGGACAUCUUGAAGUGGGGGCUUCCAGGUUGUAGGUGGAUUUAAAGAUUUCCUGAUUGGCAGCUGGUUGGAAGGGUUAAGCUCUGCCUGAAGUCAGAAAGGAAUGGAAUGCUUGGGGUUAAGAUAAAGGAGGUUGUGGAAGCCCAGGUUCUUGAAGCUUCCAGGUAGAGGCUUCAGAGAGAAUAGAUGGUAAAUGUCUCUUAGCAGACCUUAAACGGUGUCAGAUGCUUCGUUUAAUCUCUCCUUGUUCAGGAAAAGACCUGGGAAGGGAUGGGGAUGCCCCAUAGAAUGUAAAUUCUCCCCACAAGAGACAGCUGGGCAGGGCCAUUCCAAAAUAUGUGAAAUAUAUUUUGGGGUAAAAUAUUUUUAUUUCCUUUAGGGCCUGCUGUCAUGUGAUGCUGUACCAGAGUUAGGUUGGAAUUUGGUAUCUCACUGAUGCAAAGAGUCCCUUCUGUCAGUCUUAAGGUCUCUGUUUUAAUGUUAAUGCUCUUCAGUUUUGCCUGAGCGCCAAAGGGAGGAAAGUAUAAUGAGGCAUGUCUGACUUCCUCCUUCCCAUCACGGCCUGAACUAGUUUUUCUGGUUCCUCCAAGAGCAGAGUCCAUUCAGUGCAUCAGGAGGCUUAGAAUUUUAGUUGGUUUAUACAUUUAAGAUUCCUUCAUGUCUUUUCAUGGCUUGAUAGUGCAUUUCUUUUUAGCACUGAAUAGUAUUCUAUCAUCUGGAUGUACCAGCUUAUCCAUUCACCUGCUGAAGGGCAUCUUGGUUGCUUCCAAGUUCUAGCAUUUCCGAAUAAAGCUGCCAUAAACAUCCAUAUGUAAGUUUUUUUGUGGACAUAAGUUUUCAAGUCAUUUGGUUUCAAGUCAUUUGGAUAAAUAGAACCGUGAUUGCCGGCUUGCAUGGUGAGAGUGUUUAGUUUUAUAAGAAACUGCCAAACUGUCUUCUGAAAUGGCUGCACCAUUUUCCCACCAGCAGUGAACGAGAGUUCCUGCUGCUCCAUGUCCUUGCCAGCAUCUGGUGGUGGGGGUCUGGGUUUUGUCAGUUCUGAUAGGUGUGUGGCAGUGUCUUGUUGCUGUCUUAAUUUGCAUUUCCCUGAUGACAGAUGUUGUGGAGCAUCUUUUCAGAUGCUUAUUUACCAUCUCCAUGUCUUUGGUGAAGUGUCUGUUAAAGUCUUUUGCUCAUUUUUUAUAGGGCUGUUUUCUUAUUGUUGGGUUUUAAGAGUUCCUUGUAUAUUUUGGACAACAAUCCUUUAUCAGAUGUGCCUUUUCCAAAUAUUUUCUCCAAGUCUAUGGCUUUUCCUCUCAUUCUCUUGAAUGUUUUAUUUGUAUUCCACAUUCCUGAGGGACACGCCAUAGUCCCAAUAGUGAUAGUAGCUCACUUGGGGGAGAUUUUAUGACAAGGGAAUAGGUUAGAUGUGAACCUCCUGAGACCUGUAUGUUUUCUUCUCCAUUCACACCACCACAUUUAGGAACCGCUCUACCGGACCAGUGUAGUACUUUGAGGAUAAAUUAUAUAUUUUUUUAAUGUUCAGCCAUCCAUUCAGGCAUUCAGGUAUGAUUUUUCUCUUUAUUUAUUCAAAUCUUGUUUUUAAUGUAAUUUUUAAGGAAACUUGUAACUUGUUCUUUUGGACAUUUUAACUAUGGUUCUUGUGAAUGGCAUUUCUUUUUCUAUUGUCUAACUGUAAUAAAGCCAUUUAUUUUUUAUUUCUUUUAUAUUCAGCCAUUUUUUGUUAGGUCUAAUCGUUCUUUGAUGCUCUCCCAUUUUCUAGUUAUGUAGUCAUUGUCUAAAAGUAAUUAUAUAAUCUAUAAUUCAGUUUAUAUAUUUAGCACAUACUUAUUUAAUUAUAUAGUGAUAAAAAUUAUAUUUUCCUUUCCAGUAACUGUAACUUUUAUUUCUCUCUUAUGCAUUGUCUUGAUUAUAACUUAACAAUUAAUUGUCAGUAAGUAGUAAUGUUAGAGGCUGCCCAAUCCUCUUCCUGACAUCAGUGGGUUGUGCCAACUAGAAUGUCAUUUAUUUUGAUAGUACAGGUUGAGCAUCUCUAAUCUAAAAAUGUGAAAUGCUCCAAAAUUCAAAACUUUUUGAAUGCUGACAUGAUGAUCGACAAAAAUGCCCAUUGGAGCAUUUUGGAUUUUGGAUUUUCAGUUUAGGGAUGCUCAACUGGUAUAAUGCAAAUAUUUCAAAAUCCCAAAAUAUCUGAAAUCUGAAAUACUUCUGGUUCCAAGCAUCUCAGAUAAGGGGCACUCAAACUGUACUUUCAGUGUGCUAAUAUAGACAACACUUUACAUGCAUAAUGUAUAUACUCAUAGUUUUAAUCAGAGAUUUCCUAAUUUUACAUUUUUUUCUGUCUGAAUGAUUGCUAAGUGAGCAGUUACAAAGUCAUAGAAAAGAUAGAGCAGAAAAGACACUGAGAAUGAGGGGAAGAGAACCUAUCAGUGUGCUUGUACUUGGAUCUCUGGCUGUGCACAGAACAUACAUCAGUGCCGUCUUCUCUUUGGUGAACUUCAGGCCAAGGAGGCUCUGUGUGGAUUCCCACAAGGUUACAGAACUGGUUCAGGGAGCAAGUUUCCGAGGUUGGAAAGAAGUGACUUCACUGUUUAACAAAGAUGAUGAGCAGCAUCUCCUGGAAAGAUGUAAAUCUCCCAAGUCCAAAGGAACUAACUUACGAUUAAAAGAAGAGUUGAAGGCAGAGAAGAAAUCUGGAUUUUGGGACAAUUUGGUUUUAAAACAGAAUAUACAGUCUAAAAAACCAGAUGAAAUUGAAGGUUGGGAGCCUCCAAAACUUGCUCUUGAAGACAUAUCGGCUGACCCUGAGGACACCGUGGGUGGCCACCCAUCCUGGUCAGGCUGGGAGGAUGACGCCAAGGGCUCGACCAAGUACACCAGCCUGGCCAGCUCUGCCAACAGCUCCAGGUGGAGCCUGCGCGCGGCAGGGAGGCUGGUGAGCAUCCGACGGCAGAGUAAAGGCCACCUGACAGAUAGCCCGGAGGAGGCGGAGUGAGGGGGGCUGCGUGGCAAGUGUGCCCCGACAUGGUGGCCUUUUAUGAGUAUACCAUGUAGUUGUUGAGUCUUUUCCGCGUUAGAAAGAAUAGAGAGUCUACUUUUUGCCUAUAUUUGAUAUUUGGACCUCUGUUUCUUUAUUUAAUGAACUCUCACACACACUGUGACUCCUUGGUGAACACGUGCAGGGAUUGUACAUUUGAUUGCCUUAUUGCAGAAAUAUUCACCUAUCAGUCCAUGUUUUGCAGAAACUGGAGAUGUGAAUUUAUGAUGCUCUCCCAUAAUACAGCAGUAAUGAUUUGCAGUUUCUCACAAAAUGAUUUUCAUGCUGCUCUGUGUUGUAGUUCUGUUUCAGAACUUCCGUACCUUUUUCUUGUAUGUAGCACGUAUAAAUGCAGCUGUCAUGCAGUUCUUUUCUUUUGCUAGAAAAUUAGUCAGGAGGUAAGAUGAAUCUUCCAAAGUUAUGUUAAAUUUUGUUUAACUUGACAAAUUAAACUUUGUUCUUAUUAAACAAAUACGUAAACAAAUACUGGAAAAGCAAAGCUUAUAUUUGGGAGUAAAAUGUAUCUUAAAAUGCAUGUUCAUCUUUUGCUGAGGGAGGAAUAGCUUCUUGUAUGUCCACUGGAUAGUAACAGUGGUUCUUUUUUGGAAUUUUAUUUUUACCUCUUUUGAACUUCUAAAUCGGUCCCUUUAUUUUCUUAAAACAUUUGCUCUCUUUUUUGUUUACAGAUUAAAGAAGUAUGGAUCAAUUUUAGUCAGUUGAUAAUUUCAUUUAGGAAACAUUGUCUUGCUCAUUAUAGAGAGUUAAGACUGUGCAUAAAAUACUGAAGUGCCUCUUUUUUAUUAGGCUCAUAUGUUUGUUCUUGCAAAGCGAGAUGCCUAUUGUGAUUGGUGUUAGAUCUGUAAGAAGCUGUGUUUUUUCCACAAGAAUAAUCGACGACCGGUUUGAGAGCAUCUCUCGCGUUCUUUUUCUGUCUGCUUACUGUCCUUGACAAUGUGAUCCUGCACAGUAUCAGGUGCCAGUUAUGCGUCCCUGGAAGGUUGGCUCUUAUCAGCAAGUCCUGCAGAUAUCUCUUAGAUAAAAGUGGUUUGAAAGAAAAGGUAUAUUUUUCUUUUUUGUUUAAAAGUAAAAUAAAACCUCCAGUUACACUGUGCAUUCCCCUCACGUAAAAACAAGACAAAAACCCUUUCCUGAGUUGCUCGGCAUGCACUCCUGUGCUGUUUCAUGCAUGUGGAUGUUCCUUCCGUUUGUUCCUGUGGAAUAACUGAGUGUGCCUGAUGGCAGAACACACUGCAGUGUUAUCAGUGUCUGCAUGUUUUUUAAUAGAACAGGUUUACUUGAUCUGUCAUCUGUUAUGCAAAAAACAGCAAUUACUUUUGCAUCCAUCUAGCUAAAUCUAUAAUCUGUGUCAAUCACUUAUACCUAUCAAUCAUCCGUAUCUAUUCACCUGUCCUCUAUGUCUGUCUUCUCUCAGUCUACAUCCAUCUAGCCUUCUGUCAAUCAUCUACUUUUUUUUUUAAUAGAACAAGAAGUUUACUUAUCAAGUCUUGAAAGGGGGACAUGUUUCAAUUGGUGUUCAAACAAAAAUUCCAGCUUGUAUUAGAACCUUGAAAUGGUGAAGUUGUGGAGGUUUUCUUUGUUCCAUAAUACAGAGACAAGUUCAUAAUUUUUAGUAUAACAGCUAAGUUGACAAAUUCUAAGUUUCCUCAGGUAAAUAGUCAUAACUGUCCUUUUCCCUAGAGAAGUGCUUGCUGGGAUAGUAAAAACAUACACCAUUUCAUGACUUCUGCAAAUACUUUCCAGCGGAAGUCAGUGUAGGUUUGUUUUUGGCUAACAUGGUCUUGCUGCGCAGGAAUGUAAACACUGUGUUUGAAACUCUGGAAAUCACGUGUGUGGGGAGAUGGGGACGCUUCCCAUGUUGUGGGGAGCUCUGUGGCUGUGAUGGCUGCAGUUGCCGUGCCUCUGUUGGAACGCUAAGUGCCUGCAACUCACGUCAAUCAUAGAAUUGUGACGCACAGUUGGCAAAAUAGUUCUUUAUGCUAUUUCUCAAAAUUUGAGGACAAACCCAGAUUGGGAUUGGAAUAUGCACUGUAAAUCAAAUUUUUCUUAUCUACAAAGACUAAUGUAAAAAUGAUUUUUUCUUCUGUGCCUGAUUAAAUUAACUGUGGUUUUUAAUAUAAAUAUUUAUUGGUGUGCUUUGGGAGAAAAAUUAUCUUUUCUUGAAAGAAGUUAUCAAAGCAAAUUUAUUAUCUUCACAAGUUAAUGGGAGAAUGUGGUUUUGAUUCUGGGUGUUUGAAUUGUGUAAACACACAGCUUCCUUGUGUGAAGAGAGUUGUCCUGUGCUCCUUCUACUGUACUUUUUUUAUUUUUUAAUAGGAAAGUGAUGUGCUUCAGAGAAGGGUUCCUCCUUAAUGUUGAGGUUUUUUAAAAAUAAAAAUACUGUUUUUAAGCUC